CUUCCUGCAGAAAAUAUAGCAGAAAGCGGAAUACCUCUUGCGAAUCCUUCCGCACUAGGAAGCCAUAAAAAUUGGGCCUUGAGAGACAGUUUGAGGUAAGGCGUUGUAUAUAUUGCAGAUAGCUCUGAGGUUUUUGGAGUGUACCAUGCUGUCUUCCUGGCAAGGAGGCCCAAGACCGCGGCAACUACUGCUCUGGCUUCUGAUCCUCGCAGCCUGGGAGACGGGUAGUGGCCAGCUCCACUACUCCGUCCCCGAGGAAGCAAAACACGGCACCUUCGUGGGCCGCAUCGCUCAGGACCUGGGGCUGGAGCUGGCGGAGCUGGUGCCGCGCCUGUUCCGGGUGGCGUCCAAAAGACACGGGGACCUUCUGGAGGUAAAUCUGCAGAAUGGCAUUUUGUUUGUGAAUUCUCGGAUCGACCGCGAGGAGCUGUGUGGGCGGAGCGCGGAGUGCAGCAUCCACCUGGAGGUGAUCGUGGACAGGCCUCUGCAGGUUUUCCAUGUGGAGGUGAAGGUGAGGGACAUUAACGACAACCCGCCCAUAUUCCCUGAAAGCAAGAAACGAAUAAUCAUUGCAGAAUCUAGACCUCCGGAAACUCGAUUUCCACUAGAUGGCGCAUCCGAUGCAGAUAUUGGAGUAAACUCGGCAUUGACCUACCGACUGGAUCCCAACGAUUAUUUCACUUUGGACGCACAAAACAGUCUUGAGCAAAUGUCUUCAUUAUCACUUGUACUGAGGAAAACACUGGACAGAGAGGAAAUUCAGGAACAUAGUUUAUUACUGACAGCCAGUGAUGGAGGUAAACCCGAGCUGACUGGCACAGUUCAGCUGCUCAUCACGAUUCUGGACGUGAAUGACAACGCCCCGGAAUUUUACCAAUCCGUUUAUAAAGUGACGGUGUUAGAGAACGCCUUCAAUGGAACAUUAGUGAUCAAGCUAAAUGCCACAGAUCCUGAUGAUGGUACAAAUGGAGAUAUAGUUUACUCAUUUAGAAGGCCUGUAUGGCCUGCAGUGGUAUAUGCAUUUACCAUAAAUCCGAACAAUGGAGAAAUUAGGACAAAAGGCAAACUAGAUUUCGAAGAAAAGAAAUUAUAUGAAAUAUCCGUGGAGGCAGUUGACAAAGGAAAUAUUCCAAUGGCGGGUCAUUGUACCCUUUUGGUGGAAGUACUAGAUGUAAAUGAUAACGCCCCAGAGGUUACCAUCACUUCUUUGUCACUCCCCAUCAGAGAAGACACUCAGCCUAGCGCCAUUAUUGCCCUAAUCAGUGUGUCCGAUCGUGACUCUGGCUCAAAUGGACAGGUCACCUGCACCUUGACGCCGCAUGUCCCCUUCAAGCUGGUGUCCACCUACAAGAACUACUACUCAUUAGUGCUGGACAGCGCCCUGGACCGCGAGAGCGUAUCAGCCUAUGAACUGGUGGUGACCGCGCGGGACGGGGGCUCGCCUUCGCUGUGGGCCACGGCCAGCGUGUCGGUGGGGGUGGCCGACGUGAACGACAACGCGCCGGCGUUCGCGCAGCCCGAGUACACGGUGUUCGUGAAGGAAAACAAUCCGCCGGGCUGCCACAUCUUCACGGUGUCUGCUCAGGACGCGGACGCACAGGAGAACGCGCUGGUCUCCUACUCGCUGGUGGAGCGGCGGGUGGGCGAGCGUGCGCUGUCGAGCUACGUGUCGGUGCACGCGGAGAGCGGCAAGGUGUACGCGCUGCAGCCGUUGGACCACGAGGAGCUGGAGCUGUUGCAGUUCCAGGUGAGCGCGCGCGACUCUGGCGUGCCGCCUCUGGGCAGCAACGUGACGCUGCAGGUGUUCGUGCUGGACGAGAACGACAACGCUCCGGCGCUGCUGACGCCCGGGGCUGGCAGCGCGGGAGGCACAGUGAGCGAGCUGAUGCCGCGGUCGGUGGGUGCAGGCCACGUGGUGGCGAAGGUGCGCGCGGUGGACGCCGAUUCGGGCUACAAUGCGUGGCUUUCGUAUGAAUUGCAGCUGGCGGCGGUCGGCGCGCGCAUCCCGUUCCGCGUGGGGCUGUACACUGGCGAGAUCAGCACGACGCGCCCUCUGGACGAGGUGGACGCGCCGCACCACCGCCUUCUGGUGCUGGUGAAGGACCACGGUGAGCCCGCGCUGACGGCCACGGCAACGGUGCUGUUGUCGCUGGUGGAGAGCGGCCAAGCGCCACAGGCUUCGUCGAGGGCGUCGGCAGGCGCUGUGGGUCCAGAAGCGGCGCUGGUGGAUGUCAAUGUUUACUUGAUCAUUGCCAUCUGCGCGGUGUCCAGCCUGUUGGUGCUCACGUUGCUGCUGUAUACUGCGCUGCGGUGCUCGGCACCGCCCACCGAGGGCGCGUGCGCGCCGGGCAAGCCCACUCUAGUGUGCUCCAGCGCGGCAGGGAGUUGGUCGUACUCGCAGCAGAGGCGGCCGAGGGUGUGCUCUGGGGAGGGCCCGCAUAAGACGGACCUCAUGGCCUUCAGUCCCAGCCUUCCUCCUUGUCUGGGUUCUGCAGAGGGAACAGGCCAGAGGGAGGAGGACUCAGAAUGCUUGAAAGAGCCACGACAGCCCAACCCUGACUGGCGUUACUCUGCCUCCCUGAGAGCAGGCAUGCACAGCUCUGUGCACCUAGAGGAGGCUGGCAUUCUACGGGCUGGUCCAGGAGGGCCUGAUCAGCAGUGGCCAACAGUAUCCAGUGCAACACCAGAACCAGAGGCAGGAGAAGUGUCCCCUCCAGUCGGUGCGGGUGUCAACAGCAACAGCUGGACCUUUAAAUACGGACCAGGCAACCCCAAACAAUCCGGUCCCGGUGAGUUGCCCGACAAAUUCAUUAUCCCAGGAUCUCCUGCAAUCAUCUCCAUCCGGCAGGAGCCUACUAACAGCCAAAUUGACAAAAGUGACUUCAUAACCUUCGGCAAAAAGGAGGAGACCAAGAAAAAGAAGAAAAAGAAGAAGGGUAACAAGACCCAGGAGAAAAAAGAGAAAGGGAACAGCACGACUGACAACAGUGACCAGUGAGGUCCUCAAAUGGAAACAAGCCACUUAGCCAGUUUUUGUAAUAAUGGCAAAUCUCUCCCAUGUAGCAAUUCCCUGCUCCUUUUUCCUAUCUACAUGAGCCCUCUUAGAGACCUCAGAAAUCUGCAGAAAGUUCCCUGUGUCUGUCUAGAACGCAUUUAACAGGUUUUGUCGUAAAAGCUUUACUAAGUCUGGUGUUAACUCUUUCUCUCCACUCUGGCUUGUUUUCAGAACCUAAAAAGCAGACCCAAGUUUCCUUUCUCCUCCGCCGCAAAGGAGAGGCUUCCCAGCCCCGCCAGUGAGAGGUUGGACUCUCUGCCCUGUGCUCCGGGGAUCCUGUCUUGAUGACACUUGCAGGGCAGGCUGAAAAGUUUUGAGAUUGAGCAGCUUGGGAGUUUGUGGCCACUGGGUAUGUGUGGCUACCGCGGGUAUGCGAGUGCCAGAUAUUGGCUGAGACGAGCCAGCUUAGACUAAUUGGUACAAGGAAGGCAAGAAAACAAAGACAAAUAAACAGCGGAAGUUAUCAGUAUGGAGGGGAAGUGUAAACUUAAAGGGACCAGACUUUCUAAAUCUUACAACUCAAGAGGUGGCAGCCACCCUCUAGGAGACAAAACUACCCCCACUGACAAGGCUUUAGGAGACCCUAAAGUCUGUUGGCUGUGACGUCAUUAUACCUAAAAUCUGCAUCAUACCUGCAAGCCAACAGUUCAGUGUUUUAACAGAGAACCACCCUGGGAAACAGAAGCAGAUCUGAUGUGUUUCCUAUACAUGUCCUGUGCUCACUUUAUUAAAAAUUCUUUUGCACACAAUGUUUAUGAAAAGGCCAGAUCCUUUUCCAAUACUUAUGCAAAAGCAAAAGAAAACCCCGACACCUCACCUUUCGCUGUUUGUUGUUUCAUAGAUUUAUUUAAAAAAAGAGAAAGUCUAUAGCUAUAAAUCUUUAAAGAGAAAUAUGAAUACAAUUCCCCUAAACUCUCCUCAAAAGAGAAUUCAGUCUACAGCCAUUUAAAUGAUCAUUGCUGCUACAGAAGUGCUUUAAGAGAAUUGCCUGAAACAUCUGUAUUAUAUCGGCCACCUGCCAAUCACAGCUUUACUCUUUCAGGUCACUCUGGGGCUGCCUCUUGCAUGUAUUACUAAAUAAAAUGAUCUCUCUUUCUCUCUCUCUCUCUCUUUUCUAAGAAACAAUUAUGUGCACUUUGAUACACAACCUUCUCUAACCAACUAUAUAUCAAGACCCAAAAAUUGAAGAAAAAUAUUGUUUUCUCAUACAGUGAGCAGAUUUUUCAAUCUACUAAUUCUGUGACUUGUCUUGGUGUGCUAGCCUACACCUUCUCUUUGGUUUAGUUUUCCUUUUCUAUAACACUCUGAAUUGCUAAUCUUACUAACACCUAUGAUGUUACCUGAAAUCAAUCUCCCAUAUGUAUGCUGUAUGCUAUGCUAAGACUCCUGAAAUAUACUUACUCUGUGCUUGUGUAUGUGAAUGUUAAUGCAACUAUUACCUAGAGUGAACUUUAAGCUUUAUUGUUGAAUGUAAUUCCAUUAUAUUUCCUUUUGUACACCUGUGAAAAAGUGGAGUAGUGUUUUUUUAACCAUUGUUAAUCAGCUUUUGUGUAUGAAAGACACAGUAAAAUUUCUUUCUUAAAUCAAGAUACUGGUGAUUCAAGGAAUUUUAUUUAUGGUCCAGCCAAGAGCCAUCUCGUGCCAAGACUUCUGCUGGCAAGGGAAUGGAUAAAGCUGUUUUGUUCUAGUAACAAUUUUGGAAUGAAUACUGACAAUAUUCCAUGAGGGUGUGCAAGCACAAAUUUUACCAAUCUGACCUCUUUGAAGUUGCAGAAUGCUUUGAAAUUCUAAUGGUAUCUGAAAUAUCAGCUCAUAGAAAGUAACAAAAUUUGCUGUCACCUUAAAUAAGACAUUUUAAUUUUGUUAUAAUGUACAAUUUAGAAGUUUGAUUAAUUAUAUUAUCUAUUUAGGCAUUAAUAUAAAAGAGGUAGGAGUCUGUUAUUUAAAAAAAGCAUUAAAUUUAAAAAAAAACUGUCUUGUCUACUUUUAGCUUCAUUCUCCCAUAUUUUGAAGGGUGUGUAACUUCAGCUCUGCAGGAUUGCAUGGGGUAAAACUUGUUACCAACACAUGUGAACCAUUGCUACAUUGUAGGUUGUGAUCAUUUUGCCCCACUGAAGCCCAUGUAUCUGACCUUACGUGCCUUUUGAACUAGGAGAAUCGGGCUAAUUUAUUAAUGAUGAUAAUUAUAAUGUAUCUGUACAGCACUUUUUACAUUUGCGAAGUGCUUUCCAAUCCAUGUUAGUUACUAGUUAUUACAGCUGUAAGGAUAAAACACGUCAUGUGGAUUCAUUUUGAAUUGGUGCUAUUGGUAUUUCCUCUGUUAUUGCUAAUAAAUGAAAAUGGUGGUAUGAAA